AAAGGUCCUCCUGGGGGAGAACAGAGUCCCGAACACCAUGGCCGUCUGGCUUGCCCAGUGGCUGGGCCCUCUGCUCUUGGUUUCCCUCUGGGGACUCUUGGCUCCAGCCUCCCUUCUUAGGCGCCUGGGUGAGCACAUUCAGCAGUUUCAGGAGAGCUCUGCCCAGGGCCUGGGCCUGAGCCUGGGGCCAGGUGCUGCAGCCCUCCCAAAAGUGGGGUGGCUGGAGCAACUGCUGGACCCCUUCAACGUGUCCGACAGACGAUCCUUCCUACAGCGUUACUGGGUGAAUGACCAACAUUGGGUUGGCCAGGAUGGACCCAUAUUCCUGCAUCUAGGGGGUGAGGGCAGCCUUGGGCCUGGCUCAGUGAUGAGAGGCCAUCCCGCAGCCUUGGCCCCAGCCUGGGGCGCCCUGGUGAUAAGCCUGGAACACAGAUUUUAUGGCCUGAGUAUACCUGCUGGAGGCCUGGAAAUGGCCCAGCUCCGCUUCUUGUCCAGCCGCCUUGCGCUGGCUGAUGUGGUCUCUGCCCGCCUGGCACUUUCCCGCCUCUUUAACAUCUCCUCCUCCAGCCCCUGGAUCUGCUUCGGAGGCUCCUAUGCCGGCUCCUUGGCCGCCUGGGCCCGGCUGAAGUUCCCCCAUCUCAUUUUCGCGUCGGUCGCCUCCUCCGCCCCGGUGCGGGCCGUGCUGGAUUUCUCCGAGUAUAAUGACGUGGUAUCCCGAAGCCUAAUGAGCACCGCGAUCGGCGGGUCCCUGGAGUGCCGGGCGGCGGUGUCCGUCGCCUUCGCUGAAGUGGAGCGGCGGCUGCGCUCGGGUGGGGCGGCUCAAGCAGCAUUGCGGACGGAGCUGAGCGCUUGCGGGCCCCUGGGCCGCGCUGAAAACCAGGCGGAGCUGUUGGGGGCGCUGCAGGCACUGGUGGGAGGUGUAGUGCAGUAUGAUGGGCAGACGGGAGCGCCGCUAAGCGUGCGACAGCUCUGCGGACUUCUCCUCGGGGGCGGGGGCAACCGCAGCCACUCCACGCCCUACUGCGGGCUUCGUCGGGCGGUGCAGAUUGUCUUGCACAGCCUGGGCCAGAAGUGUUUAAGCUUUUCCCGAGCAGAGACAGUGGCACAGCUGAGGAGCACAGAACCUCAACUGUCUGGUGUGGGUGACCGGCAGUGGUUGUAUCAGACAUGUACCGAGUUCGGCUUCUAUGUCACCUGUGAGAAUCCCAGAUGUCCUUUCUCCCAGCUCCCAGCACUGCCCUCCCAGCUAGACCUAUGUGAGCAGGUGUUUGGGCUCUCAGCCUUGUCAGUAGCCCAGGCUGUGGCUCAGACGAACUCCUACUACGGUGGCCAGACCCCUGGGGCUAACAAAGUGCUGUUUGUUAAUGGGGACACAGACCCCUGGCAUGUGCUAAGUGUAACACAGGCUUUAGGAUCCUCAGAAUCAACUCUUCUUAUCCGCACUGGCUCCCACUGCUUGGACAUGGCACCUGAGAGGCCCUCAGACUCCCCCAGCCUCCGCCUAGGGCGCCAGAACAUCUUCCAGCAGCUACAGACCUGGCUCAAGCUGGCAAAGGAGAGCCAGAUUAAGGGUGAAGUCUGAAUCUCAUACCCUUUCCACUCCCUGCAUGGUCACCUCAGUCCUGGACAUACUUGUUCACUGAACAAAAGAAAGCAGCUUGUUUUGAAAGAAGAAACUCCCAGGAAUUGGAAUUCAGCACCUGUUCCGCACGUAAUUGGCAUGUGUCUGCAAACAUCCUUAUUCCCAACUUAAAGUGCUUUAUUGCAGAGAGUUAUGGAAAUAUAAGUGGAUGAUUAUUCUCAUUGUAAAUAUUGGUAUUUUGAAUGUUAAAUGUCAAACAAAUGUGACUUAUGCUGGUGCCCUCGCCCUGCUGAUCAGAUUCUGGUUCAAAUUCUGCCACUCCAGCUCCUGGGUUAGGGGCUUUGCUGUAAGUUUCUUUUUCUGGACUUUAGAUCCUGAACCUGUCCUUGCUUCUCAGUUUCUCUCACUGUACCCCUUUCCCUCAGUCUCUUCCUCUCUCUUUCCCCUGUCACUAUUUGUCUUUCUAAUCUCCUUCUGUUUCUCUGAAUAUCUUCAUUUCUAUCUCUGUGUUUCUGUCUAUUUCUCUGUUUAUCUUUCUGUCCUUCAAUCUGUGUUUUUGUUUCUGGCUCUCCGUCAGUGUCUUUUUCUCUCCUCUCUCUCUUGCUCUGCCAUGGCUAUUUCCACUGCUCUAUUUCUGACUCUCAUUUUUGGUCUCUGUGUGUCUCCUAGUCACUUUCUUUCUCACUCUGUCUCUGUCUCUAUUUCUGUCUCUCCUCUGCUGUGUCCUCAAUCUCUCUGUCUCCCUGAGGCUCUAUUUCUGUCUCUCCUCUGCUGUGUCCUCAAUCUCUCUGUCUCCCUGAGGCUCUAUUUCUGUCUCUGAUGCUCUUCUUCUGUGUCUCUAUUUCUCUUCCUGUCACUUAAUCUUUUCCUUCUCUAUCUCUCUUAUUUAGUCUUCCUUCCACACCCUUCACUCACCAUCUUUUCCCACAAUCAAAUAUCACUCCCUGGUACUUCCAGCUUCCAACUCUAGGGAUUCAUGAUUCUGGUGGAGAUUCCUUCUUCCAGGGCCUGGGAGGAUAGGGCUAAUCCCAAGGGUGCCUGCUUAGGCUAUGUUAGCUGUGACAGGAACCUGCCAUAGAUUUGCACUGUUCUUUCCUAAAGAUCAAUUAUUUUCAGCAAUAAAUACUUCUCAGCUUUUUGUAUGUCUUUGUAUGCACAGAGAUGGUAGUUUUAGAGUUUUAUCCAGUUUCAUAUUUCCUUGUGGGUAAGAGGCAACCUCCUCAUGCUGUCAUACCAAAGUCAAUCUCCACUACACUUUAGUUCUGCCUGUUCUUGAUCUUUAUAUAAAUGGAAACUUGCAGUAUA